GAGUCAAGGCAACUGAAGUUUUGCAGCCAGUCUCUGUCUUUGCUUCUGGAAGGAUGACUUCUGACUGCUCCUCCACACACUGCUCUCCUGAGUCCUGUGGCACGGCUUCCGGUUGUGCACCUGCCUCAAGCUGCUCCGUGGAAACAGCUUGUCUCCCCGGUACCUGUGCUACAUCCCGAUGUCAGACUCCAAGCUUCCUAUCCAGGUCUCGCGGGCUGACUGGUUGCCUCCUGCCAUGCUACUUUACUGGGAGUUGUAAUAGUCCCUGCUUGGUGGGGAACUGUGCCUGGUGUGAGGAUGGGGUGUUCACUAGCAAUGAGAAGGAGACGAUGCAGUUCCUGAAUGACAGACUCGCCAGCUAUCUGGAGAAGGUGCGCAGCCUGGAGGAGACCAACGCAGAGCUGGAAUCCAGGAUCCAAGAACAAUGUGAACAGGAUAUCCCAAUGGUGUGCCCGGAUUAUCAGCGUUACUUCAACACCAUUGAAGAUCUCCAACAAAAGAUCUUAUGCACGAAAGCAGAGAAUUCUAGACUUGCUGUACAGCUUGACAACUGCAAACUGGCCACUGAUGACUUUAAGUCAAAGUACGAGAGUGAACUGUCCCUUCGCCAGCUGUUAGAGGCUGACAUCAGCAGCCUGCAUGGGAUCCUGGAGGAACUGACCCUGUGCAAAUCUGAUCUGGAGGCCCAUGUGGAGUCUCUGAAGGAAGAUCUCCUUUGCCUUAAGAAAAACCAUGAAGAGACGAAGAAACUGAGGCCCUUCUAAGUGGUGAAAAGAGAUUCAGCCCAGGCAAUCUGAAUCAAAAUCUCACACUUUUACCCACUGCUCCAAAAAACAGAAGUAGAAUGCCAUUGGAUGUCAAAUGGAUUUUUCCCCACCAUUCUGUGACAUUCUUUACACCAUCCCACUUUCAGGAAGUCAACUUGCUUCGUGAACAGCUUGGCGACCGCCUCAGUGUGGAGCUGGACACUGCCCCCACCCUUGACCUCAACAGGGUCCUGGAUGAGAUGCGCUGUCAGUGUGAAACGGUGCUUGCCAACAAUCGCAGAGAAGCUGAAGAAUGGUUGGCUGUUCAGGUCAGUACCCAGAUUGAAAAAAUGUCAGGCUUACAGACUUCUGCCUUUUUUGAAUUCUCUAAUGGUGUCUGUGUUUCAGACAGAAGAGCUGAAUCAGCAGCAACUGUCCAGCGCGGAGCAGCUGCAGGGCUGCCAGAUGGAGAUCUUGGAACUGAAACGCACAGCCAGUGCUCUGGAAAUUGAGCUCCAAGCACAGCAAAGCCUGGUGCGUGAGGCAAAGGCAGUGUCCGUUGUGUCACUGAUAAGUCAGGCCCUGAGAUGUUAAGCCCUCUUCCAUAUCCGAGGAUCACAUUUCCUUGCCUUUCCCGAGUACUGCCGUUUACCCAGCUAUUAAUAGAAGCAGAAGUGACAGGUCCACAGCUUGUCCUCUAAGAUGCCUUACCUUCACUCCUGGGCUUGAGUCUGAUGCUGCAGCAGCCUCCAGAGACAGGGAGGGAGAAGCAGAGCUGGAGAGAAACCUCCGGGCCAUGGUCGCUUAAGCAUUCUGGCAGGUUUUAAUUCUCAUUUGAUUCAGGCCAGUUUUCCAGGCUCACUGUUAUAUCUAAAACAAAGAAUCAUUUUCAAACAUUUCAUCCUACAGUUUCCCAGGAUCUACACUUCAACCUUAUCCUUCACUGCACCACCCCCCACUCAAGCAACAGGAACACCAUGCGUUCAAGAUGACAUGAACCAGUUCUGGUCAAGCACCACUGUGUGCAUGUCAUUAGGCCCUGCGGAGAACACCUAGAAGAACAAUAGCUGAGCAUUCAUCCUGUGAGAGGCACUAUGCUGAUUUAAGGCUCACAGUAACUUUACCGGAUAGAUACCUUUAUCCCAUGACACAGAUAAGGAAAACUGAGACUCAGAUUAAGUAACUUGCAAAGGAUGCAAUUCUAAGAGGCAAACUUGGAAGCUGAGUUCAGCCAGUUGAAUCCCAGAGUCUCUUCUCUCUCUCUUUUUAAAUUUAUUUUUAUUGAUAUAUAAUAUGCGUAAAUUUUUUUUACGUAGAUGUGAUAUUUUGUUACAUGCAUAGAAUGUGUAAUGAUCAAGUCAGGAUAUUUAGAGCAUCCAUCACCUCAAGUAUUUAUCAUUUCUAUGUGUUGGGAGCAUUUCAAGUCCUCCCAUCUAGCUAUUUUGAAAUGCACAGUGUAUUGUUGUUAACUGUAGUCACACUUCUCUGCUGUCCAACAUGAAAACAUAUUCUUUCUGUCUAACUGUAUGUUUGCACCCAUUAACCAACCUCUCUUCAUCCCCUUACCACACAUAUGCCAGUCCCAGCCUCUGGUAUCCAGAGCCUCUUCUCUUAAUAGCACUAUACUACCCCUCCCUGCCAAGAGCCCAAACUCAAUCUUUCCUCUCAUAUGUUGUGGAUAGUCCUUAAGCUUCACAAAUAUGUCAUGUAUUGCUGUAGUCAUAGUGGUGGUAGUGAUAGUUGACACGUAGAACAGUGGCAGUAUGGCUGGCACUGUUCUAAAUGCUUUACGCACAUUAACUCUUUUUUUUUUUUUUUGGACGGAGUCUCCCUCUGUCGCCCAGGCUGGAGUGCAAUGGCAUGAUCUUGACUUACUGCAAGCUUUGCCUCCCGGGUUCACACCAUUCUCCUGAGUAGCUGGGACUACAGGCGUCCACCACCGUACCCAGCUAAUUUUUUAUAUUUUUAGUAGAGACGGGGUUUCACCGUGUUAGCCAGGAUGGUCUCGAUCUUCUGACCUUGUGAUCCGCCCGCCUCGGCCUCCCAAAGUGCUGGGAUUACAGGCCUGAGCCACCGCGCCCAGCCCGCAUAUUAACUCUUAAUCUUCACAACCGUCUAAUGAAACAGAUACUUUGUAUUCUCCACUAUACAGAGAAUAAAACUGAGACUCACAGAAGCUAAAUAAUUUGCCAGUGGUCACAUAGCUAGAAAAGGGUAAGCAGGAAUUUGAAAGUAGGCACUCUGGCCCGAGAGACUGCACUUCAUGGUCCUUUGGACAAUGUUUCCUCCCGCAGACAGAAUCUCUGGAAUGCACCGUGGCAGAAACCGAGGCCCAGUACAGCUCCCAGCUGGCCCAAAUUCAGUGUCUGAUCGAUAACCUGGAGAACCAGCUGGCCGAGAUCCGCUGCGACCUGGAGCGACAGAACCAGGAGUACCAGGUGCUCCUGGACGUGAAGGCCCGGCUGGAGGGUGAGAUCAACACGUACUGGGGCCUGCUGGACAGCGAGGACAGCAG